GACUAAUGGCCCUAACUAAGUAUUAACCCCUGCCAAGAAAAGAGCUACUUCCUCUUGAAGUAAAUGAAGAUAGUGAUGCUUUCUCUUAAACUUUACUUAUAAAAAGCAUCAAAGGGGGGAAUGAAGCAGGAAAUAUAAAAGGAAAAACAAGUAAAGGGAAAACAAGUCCUUUCCUGACCAGUCUGACUCACUCCAAAGUCCUGCUGGAGCUAUGAUAAUUAUCUGCAAGGCCAGGCAGGGGCUCCGAAGGAGUGGGCUCCAGGAGCAGGGAUGAGAAAAACAAGUUCUCCUUAUCAGUUUCCCUGUUUGAAAUUCUCUCCCCAUAACAUUAUUCUUUGUUCUGCUCUCACAACUAUUUUUGUAACUAUUUCUGCAAGUCUGUAAAGAUUUUGUAAGUUCUUGUUUUUCUUUCUGUAGCAUGGCAAGGUCACAAGACAUGUUUAAGUAAGGUAGGCUCAUGUUGCAAAUCCUGUUGUAAAACCUGUCACGGUAUGAUUAACUGCCUUUGUUCUGCUUCUGUAAGACUGCUUUCUCACCUCGCAGGUUUUGCGCCAAAAACCCGACUUGCCCCUGCCUGAUGCAUGUAUAAAAGUCAAGCCCUGUCUUUGUUCAGGGCUCAGCCUUUGGAUGUUAAUCCGCUGGGCCAGUGGCCACCUAAAUAAAACCUUCCUGUUGCACCCAGUGAUCUCUCCGGCCUCCUGAUUCCCACAACAUAUAAGCAUUCCUUUUUCUCUGCAACCUAGCCCGCAUCUGUCAUUGACUUUUUAACAAUAGGCAUUCUGACUGGAUGAGAUGGUAUCUCACUGUGGUUUUUCUCUGCAUUUUUCUAAUAAUUAACAACGUGAAUUUUGUUUUCAUAUGCUUGUCAGCCACAUGUAUGUCUUCUUUUGAAAAGUAUCUGUUCAUGUUUUUGCUUACUUUUUAAUUAGGUUUUUGGUUUUCUUUUUGUUGUUGUUGUUGUUUUCUGAGAUGGAGUCUUGCUGUGUCACCAGGAUGGAGUGCAGUGGCAUGAUCUCGACUCACUGCAACCUCCACCUCCCAGGUUCAGAUGAUUCUUCUGCUUCAGUCUCCUGAGUAGCUGGGAUCACAGGGACCAUUGACAUUUAUGGAUGUGGCCAUAGAAUUCUCUUUGGAGGAGUGGCAAUGCCUGGACACUGCACAGCAGAAUUUAUAUAGGCAUGUGAUGUGAGAGAACUACAGAAACCUGGUUUUCUUGGGUGAAGGUAUUGCUGUCUCUAAGCCAGACCUGAUUACCUGUCUGGAGCAAGGAAAAGAGCCCUGGAAUAUGAAGAGACAUGAGAUGGUAGCUAAACAUUUAGUUAUGUUUUAUUAUUUUGCCCAACACCUUUGGCCAGAGCAGAACAUAAGAGAUUCUUUCCAGAAAGUGACCCUAAGAAGAUAUAGAAAAUGUGGAUAUGAGAAUUUACAGUUAAGAAAAGGCUGUAAAAGUGUGGUUGAGUGUAAACAGCACAAAGGAGAUUAUAGUGGACUUAACCAAUGUUUGAAAACUACCUUGAGCAAAAUAUUUCAAUGUAAUAAAUAUGUAGAAGUUUUCCAUAAAAUUUCAAAUUCAAAUAGACACAAGAUGAGACAUACUGAAAAUAAACAUUUUAAAUGUAAAGAAUGUCGCAAAACAUUUUGCAUGCUUUCACACCUAACUCAACAUAAAAGAAUCCAAACUAGAGUGAAUUUCUACAAAUGUGAAGCAUAUGGAAGAGCCUUUAACUGGUCCUCAACCCUUAAUAAACAUAAGAGAAUUCAUACUGGAGAAAAACCUUACAAAUGUAAAGAAUGUGGCAAAGCCUUUAACCAGACCUCACACCUUAUUAGACAUAAGAGAAUUCAUACUGAAGAGAAACCCUACAAAUGUGAAGAAUGUGGCAAAGCCUUUAACCAGUCAUCGACCCUUACUACACAUAAUAUAAUUCAUACUGGGGAAAUUCCCUACAAAUGUGAGAAAUGUGUUAGAGCUUUUAACCAAGCCUCAAAGCUUACUGAACAUAAGUUAAUUCAUACCGGAGAGAAACGUUAUGAAUGUGAAGAAUGCGGCAAAGCUUUUAACCGAUCCUCAAAACUUACUGAACAUAAGUACAUUCAUACUGGAGAGAAGCUGUACAAAUGUGAAGAAUGUGGUAAAGCCUUUAACCAGUCCUCAACCCUUACUACACAUAAGAGAAUUCAUAGUGGAGAGAAGCCCUACAAAUGUGAAGAAUGUGGCAAAGCUUUUAAACAAUUUUCAAAUCUUACUGACCAUAAAAAAAUUCAUACUGGAGAGAAACCCUACAAAUGUGAGGAAUGUGGCAAAGCUUUUAACCAACUCUCAAACCUUACUAGACAUAAGGUAAUUCAUACUGGAGAGAAACCCUACAAAUGUGGAGAAUGUGGCAAAGCCUUUAACCAGUCCUCAGCCCUUAAUACACAUAAGAUAAUCCAUACUGGAGAGAAUCCCCACAAAUGUAGAGAAUCUGGCAAAGUUUUCCACCUAUCCUCAAAACUUAGUACAUGUAAGAAAAUUCAUACUGGAGAGAAACUCUACAAAUGUGAAGAAUGUGGCAAAGCCUUUAACCGAUCUUCAACCCUUAUUGGACAUAAGAGAAUUCAUACUGGAGAGAAACCCUACAAAUGUGAAGAAUGUGGCAAAGCUUUUAACCAAUCUUCAACACUUACUACACAUAAGAUAAUUCAUACUGAAGAGAAACAGUACAAAUGUGAUGAAUGUGGCAAAGCUUCUACCUGAUCCUCAAAACUCAUUGAACACAAGAAAAUUCAUACUGGAGAGAAACCUUACAAGUGUGAAGAAUGUGGCAAAACUUCUAACCAUUUCUCAACCCUUACUAAACAUAAGAUGAUUCAUACUGGAGAGAAGUUACACAAAUGUGAUGAAUGUGACAAAGCUUUUAACCAAUCUUCAACCCUUUCUACACAUAAAAGAAUUCAUACUGGAGAGAAACCCUACAAAUGUGAAGAAUGUGGCAGAGCUUUUAAUUGAUCAUCAAACCUUAUUAAACAUAAGAAAAUUCAUAUUGGAGAGAAACCCUACAAAUGUGAAGAAUGUGGAAAAGCUUUUAACCAGUUCUCAACUCUUACUACACAUAAAAUAAUUCAUACUGGAGAGAAACCAUAUAAAUGUGAAGAAUGUGGCAAAGCUUUCAACCUAUACGUAAACCUUACUACACAUAAGAAAAUUCAUACUGGAGAGAAACCCUACAAGUGUGAAGAAUGUGGCAAAGCUUUUAGCCAAGUGUCAACUCUUACUAUACAUAAAAGAAUUCAUACUGGAGAGAAACCCUACAAGUGUGAAGAAUGUGGCAAAGCUUUUAACCAAGUGUCAACUCUUACUAUACAUAAAAGAAUUCAUACUGGAGAGAAACCUUACAAAUGUGAGGAAUGUGGCAAAACUUUCAGUCGAUGCUCAAAACUUACUACACAUAAGAAAAUUCAUACAGGAGAGAAACCUUACAAAUGUGAAAAAUGUGCUAAAGCUUUUAGCCAGUCUUCAACCCUUUCUACAUAUAAGAUAAUUCACACUGGAGAGAAAUGCUACAAAUGUGAAGAAUGUGGCAAAGUUUUUAACCGAUCUUCAAACCUUACAGACCAUAAAAAAAUUCAUACAGGAGAGAAAUCCUACAAAUGUGAAGAAUGUGACAAGGCCUUUAACCUGUCCUCAACGCUUACUAAACAUAAGGUAAUUCAUACUGGAGAGAAACUGUACAAAUGUAAAGAAUGUGGUAAAGCUUUUAAACAGUUCUCACACCUUGCUAUACAUAAUAUAAUUCAUACUGGAGAGAAACUCUACAAAUGUGAAGAAUGUGGCAAAGCUUUUAACUUAUCCUCAAACCUUACUGCACAUAAGAAAAAUCGUACUGGAGAGAAACCCUACAAAUGUGAAGAAUGUGGCAAAGCUAACCUAUCAUCAACCCUUACUCCACAUAAGACAAUUCAUAUUUGAGAGAAACCCUGCAAAUGUGAAGAAUGUGGCAAUGCUUGUAACUAAAUCUCAAACUUUACUAAACAUAAGAAAAUUAAUACUGGAAACUUUACAAACCUGAAAGAUGUGACAAUGAUUUUGACAACACCUUCAAACUUUUCUAAACAUAAAAUAAAUCAUACUGGUGAGAAAUCUUAAAAAUAUGAAGAAUGGUACAAAGCCUUUAAAUGGUUGUCACACUUGAUUGUAGGUAAGAUAAUUUAUACUGGAGGAAACUCCCAGAAGUGUGAAGAAUGUGGCAAAACUUUUAAUUUUUCACACCUUAUAGCACAGGAAAGCACUUCAGAAAAAUUGUACAAAUAUAAAUGUGGAAAAGCCAUUAAUAUCUGCUUACAUCUUACUCAACAUUAGAGAGUUAGUGCUUAAUAAAAGCAUUAUAAAAGCAAUUAGUGUAAAAUCAGAAAAUGAAAGUUUUUUUUUUUUUUUUAGAUGGAGUCUUGCUCUGUCACCCAGGCUGGAGUGCAGUGGUGUGAUCUUGGCUCACUGCAACCUCUGCCUCCCAGGUUCAAGCAAUUCUCCUGCCUUAGCCUCCAGAGUAGCUGAGACUACAGGCACACACCACCACAUUUGGCUAAUUUUUUUAUUUUUAGUAGAGACUGGCUAUCACCAUGUUGGCCAGGCUGAUCUUGAACUCCUGACCUCAAGUGAUCCACAUGCCUCUGCCUCCCAAAGUGCUGGGAUUAUAGGUGUGAGUCACUGUGCCUGACAAAUAUAAGCCUUUAAAGAGAAGAAGGUUUUCAUUUUGAAGACAAACAUUAGGUACAUAAAGAGGGUUGUAGUGUCUUUAUUUGUAUCACAGAUUUUAUUGUACACAUUAUGUACUAAAGGAAAAUCCUGAAGCAGUGCUCAAACUUUGAUCAACAUCAGGGAGUUUAUAUUGGAGAAAAACUGCAAAUGUAAUAUAUUUGGAAAAACAUUUUUCAAAAACUACUGCUUAGAAAACACCAGGGGAUUUAUACUAAAAUAUAUUUUUGCAGAUGCAGUAAGUAUAAAAGAAAUUUAAUCCAAAAUUAAGUGUGUGUAAAUAUCAGAGAAUUCACAGUAGAAAUAUCUAAGGCACUGACAUUUUAGACAUUGAACUAAUCAGUGUGCUGAGUACAGAAAAUAAUCCAAAAUUAAAGUUGGUAGAUAAAUUAUUUAUAUAUAACUUUAAAAGAGGUAGAAAUAUUUUUAGUUAUAAUUACAUUUAAAGUAUACUUUUUUCUUUGAAAAAAUUACAAAAUUUUUAAAAAGUGAAUGAUGUAAUUCAACUCAAAUUACUUCAUGCUUUUCAUUCUAUUGUAUUCACAUGUGAAAGCAUGUGAUCAAUUGCUGCUUCAUCAAAGAUAUGAGACAUUCUUUUUUGUUAGGUGGGCAAUAUUUUUUACCUUUUCUAUGGAAGAGUAAAGACAUUACAAUGUAGGAUGCAUGAUAAAAAUCUAAGUGGAGAGGCUCUUUGUGUUUAAUUUAUAAUAUUGAAUGAUGUAUGAGGGAAGUGUUCAGAGGAAUAUUCUGCAUUCUAGUGAAAAUAUCUUUUAUUUUAGUUAAAAUUAAAUUAAAAUUAGUAGUAUAUCAUUUUACUAACUGUACUUUUAUGUAAUAAAAUGCAGCACAUUUAAAAAAUUUUAGAUUAUUGUGAACUUAAUUUUUUAAUUAAACUUUUUUUUUAACAUGUUAAGACCAAUUGUGCAUUCAGUGAAGUAUUAUCAUGCCACUAACUUCAACCUAUCCCACCUUACUCAAGGGUGUUGGUAAAAGAUAGUAACAAUGUACUAUUUAAUAACAGAGUGGACUAACAUCUCUAAUAAUUUCUCUUGCCAGUGACUUUAAACUAAAGAACUUAAUUAAAGAACAUUGUUCCCAUAGGUUAAAUUUUUAUUCUUUUUCUUAUUUAAACAUAUUUUUCUUAACUUUUGUGGGUACAUAGUGUGUGUAUAUAUUUAUGCCAUAUAUGGCAUAUUUUGAUACAGGCAUAUGAAUAGGUAUUAAUCACAUCAGGGCAAAUGAAAUAUCCAUCAACUCCAGCAUUUAUCAUUUGUAUUACAAACCGAUUCUACACUUUUAGUUACUUUAAAAUGUACAAGUAAAUUGCUAUUGACUAUAGGGUCAUUUUCAUGGGUAUAAUAAAAAUUAUAUACAAGUAUAAAUAAAAUCCUGAGUCUUAAAAUUCUGAGUCCUGCUUAAACAUUUUAAAAAUUUUGUUAUGUAUUUUUCUUUGAACAUGUCUCUCUGCCUGCAAACAUAACAGAAUUUUAGUAUUGGUUUACAUAGAGUUAACUAUACCCAUAUAUUACUCUAAAAAUAAAUGUUAAGUGCAAGAAAGUUAUGGACUGUUUUUGUGUGAGUGUGAGUUUGUACCUAUUUUCAAAAGAAAAGAGCAAUAUUGGAGCAAAACAAAUAUUUUAAUAAAGUAAUGUACUAGACAACUGAAAACUUCAAAAAUGCUGAAAGUAAAUGUAUACUCUGCUUUGUAUUGAAUUCAUUACUGCCAAAUCUUCUGACUUAUGAUUCAGAAUCUCUCCAUGCAAAUUAUGUUUUUACUUGCCUGUUAGUCAUGCUAGACCUAUAAUUUUCUUGUUUCUUACCAUUUUUUUCUUUUAUACUUUAUGAGGUAUUAUGUGAGCUGUUCAUGGAUUAUAAGAAUGAUUUUUAUAAAAUUCAGUACUGCACACAAGAUAAGUUUUAGAUGUAUUUCCAAAAUUGUGUAUUAAUUAUAUUUAGUUAGAACAUUCCAUUUGUUCUUUUAAUUGGAGAAUCCUAUAUAAGCCUAUAUUUCUUAUUCUUUUCUCUUGUUAUAAUUGACAUAAGUAAAUUUAUUUAUUUAUUGAGCCAAUUUGUUCAGGUAAGAACUAGGAAUGCUUCAUAAGUCAUGAGGAUGUUUUUAUAUAUAUAUGUGGCAAACAAAUAUGACAGUGCUUGCUGUGUAACAGAUGUUCCAUAAUAACCUGUAAACAUUCCUGCUGGAGUUAGUUUGUAACUUCAAGUCAGAGAUGGAAAAUACCAAUAGUGAAGAAAUAACAUUGAUUCUUCAUGUGCAGAUAACAUUUUUUUUCCAUGCUGCAAAGCUAAAUUUUGCUGAAUUUAAAAAGAAAUUUUGGUUCUUUUAUUUCCUAAUUACCUUUAGUUUUGUUUGUCUUAUUAUGUGACUUCUGUGUAUUCAUCACAGCCCUUCUCCUUCUUUUUCUAUGUGAUGGCUACACUUUGCUCACUGUUGUCUUCAUGCCAUGUCAUUUUAUACAGUACUUUGUAGGUUUUGAUGAGAAAGUUGGUAUUUUUAAUGCACUCAAAAAUUGCUUUUUAUUGGAGAGUACUUAUCAAUAUAACUUUCUGAUCAGUUAAUUAAGAUAAAAGGCAUACAUUGUCCACAGGUGAGAGGAUUAAAUCAGUUAGCAUUAUUUUUUUCUGUUUGUAAAAGGAAAAACUUAUUAAAUUUUUAAACGGAGUUAUUAAACAGAGUUUCACUCUUAUUGCCCAGGCUGGAGUGCAAAUAUAUUGUGGCAAAUAUAAAAUUUGCUAGAAAAUACAUCUUAGAAAUUAAGUUAUAAGAGAGCAAAUGGUAAGUGAAGAAUUUUAAAUUUAAUUUUCUAUGAUAUAGCAUAACAUACAUUUCCAUGCAGAAUCUUUUAUUUUUAAAUGUGAAAUUUAAAGGUUGCAAAAUAAUAAAAUGACUUCUGUGGAUUUGAUAUUUGGAAUGAUAUUUCUUUUUUAUAUUGAUAUUACAAUUCCGAGGAAUUUUUCACUCAUUAUUUUUUUAGUGGGUGAAGGUGAGUGUACAGUUAUUGCUUUUUGUCACCUAACUAUAGUCAGCUUCUUGGUCAUUUUCUCUAGAAAACUUUUGAAGAUUAUGGCAGCUUUUUGAUUAAACAUUUUCUGUUAUUUUUAUGCAAAUUCAUUUAUUGUGUUCACAGGGUGGCCAGUCAUGAGACCAUAAGCAACAGCUGCCCUUUUAGUGUCUUUCAUGCCAUUACCAUCUGUAAUAAAUAAAUGUGUACUUUAUUCUGCAAAACAUGAUGUUUGGAAGUAUAUGUUGUCAAAUGCUUAAUUCUAGGUAAUUAAGGCUUUACCUCACAUCGUUAACAUUUUUGUGGUCAGAGUAUGUGACAUUGUCAAUGUUUUUCAAAAACACAACUACAUUAUUAUGAUCUGUAGUCACUAUGCUGUACAAAAAGAUCUCUUAAACUUAUUCCUCCUAUUAAACUAUAAUUAUGUAUUCUUUGACCAACAUCUUCCAAAACCCCCCUUUUUUCUAAAUACCUUGGUGUCUGGUGGUCACCACUUUACUCUCUACUUUAAUGGGAUUAAGUUUCUUAGAAUCCCUGUGUAAGUAAAAUCAUGAAAAAUAAUCUUUGUGUCUGGCUCAUGUAGACAAAUAUGAUGUCCUCCAGGUUAAUUCAUGUGAUUGAAAAUAAUAGAAAUUUCUUUUUUAAAGACGAAGAGUAUUCCAUUGUGUAUAUGUACCACAUUGUCUUUAUUUACUCAUAAAUGUUGAACUGUUGAUUGUGUAUUUUGGUAAUUGUGAAGAGUGUUGCAAACAACAUAGAAGCAUAAAUGUUUCUUCAUUCUGAUUUCACUUGUUUUGGAUAUAUACAGUAAAAUUGCUGUAUUGUGGUUUAAUUUUAAAUUUUUUGACAAAUUUUUGUUUUUCAUAGUGACUCUCCUCAUUCACAUUCAAACCAACAGUGUGCAAGCAUUCCUUUUCUUCAUACUUUGACUAACACUUUCUUUUCUUUUUAGUAAGAGUAAUUCUAACAGGAGUGAGUUGAUAAUCUCCUGGUUUUUCUUUUUGCUUUCCUGAUUAUAGUUGAUAUUGAGCAUUUUUUAUAUAUCUUGACCAUUUGUCUUUUCUUGAAAAAUAUUUAAGCCUUUUGCUCAUUUUUAAUAGUUAUUUGUCUUCUGUUGUAUAGUCAUUUAAGUUGUUUAUAUGUUUCUGUUAUUAACCCUUUGUCCCACGUAUGAUUUGCAAAUAUUUUCUCCCAUUUUUUUCAGUUGUCUCAUUUUGUUGAUUGUAUCAGAUUCCAUGAAGCAGCUUUUUAAUUUCAAGUAAUCUAACGUAUCUAUUUUUCUUUUGAUUUCCUUGGAUUUUGAGGUUAAAUAAUAAAAGUCACAGCCUAGAUCAA